CUCAGCAGAGACAACAUCCUGUUACACCCUCUCUUCAUGCUGAGUGAUUCUAACCUCCUCUGGAAUGAACUCCAUGCUUGCAGAGUCAUCUUCAGAAUGAGUCAGCUCCGCUUGUCCCAGGCAGGAGACUCACGAGUUGAUGUGAAAUGCGGAUUCCCUAUGAGACGGAGGACAUUGCAUGUCUCAUCCCAUCACGACCGUGUGGGUCUCGUUAUUUCAUAAGAGAGGGGGAAAAUGUGAAUUGGAAUUUUAUUUCCUAAGUACUGUUCUUGGUUUCUGACCAGCUGAUCCCAAGUUUCACAUCCUUGUCUGUGAAGCUAAACUCAAUGCUGCUGUGUGGGAAGAAGAUUUGUAAAGAAAACUCUUAGAUUGAAGAUGGAUACGUGACAAUCCCAGGGACCGCUGCACUGACUUCAUUUCCUUAGACAAGACACAGUGUAGGGCCCGGCCCGUGUUGGCCCCAGGACUCCUUUGGAAUAUAGCUGUGGACAAUGAAUCCUGCGAGCGAUGGGGGCACAUCAGAGAGCAUUUUUGACCUGGACUAUGCAUCCUGGGGGAUCCGCUCCACGCUGAUGGUCGCUGGCUUUGUCUUCUACUUGGGCGUCUUUGUGGUCUGCCACCAGCUGUCCUCUUCCCUGAAUGCCACUUACCGUUCUUUGGUGGCCAGAGAGAAGGUCUUCUGGGACCUGGCGGCCACGCGUGCAGUCUUUGGUGUUCAGAGCACAGCCGCAGGCCUGUGGGCUCUGCUGGGGGACCCUGUGCUGCAUGCCGACAAGGCGCGUGGCCAGCAGAACUGGUGCUGGUUUCACAUCACGACAGCAACGGGAUUCUUUUGCUUUGAAAAUGUUGCAGUCCACCUGUCCAACUUGAUCUUCCGGACAUUUGACUUGUUUCUGGUUAUCCACCAUCUCUUUGCCUUUCUUGGGUUUCUUGGCUGCUUGGUCAAUCUCCAAGCUGGCCACUAUCUAGCUAUGACCACGUUGCUCCUGGAGAUGAGCACGCCCUUUACCUGCGUUUCCUGGAUGCUCUUAAAGGCGGGCUGGUCCGAGUCUCUGUUUUGGAAGCUCAACCAGUGGCUGAUGAUUCACAUGUUUCACUGCCGCAUGGUUCUAACCUACCACAUGUGGUGGGUGUGUUUCUGGCACUGGGACGGCCUGGUCAGCAGCCUGUAUCUGCCUCAUUUGACACUGUUCCUUGUCGGACUGGCUCUGCUUACGCUAAUCAUUAAUCCAUAUUGGACCCAUAAGAAGACUCAGCAGCUUCUCAAUCCGGUGGACUGGAACUUCGCACAGCCAGAAGCCAAGAGCAGGCCAGAAGGCAACGGGCAGCUGCUGCGGAAGAAGAGGCCAUAGCUGCUCCAGCCGGGGCUCCGGGGCGGCAGCAGAGCUGGCACACCGAUUCUGGGAAGCCCCGCGAAUGAUGGCUUUUGAAUUAAUGAGGCAGUGAAUGUUUUGUGUUUACUUCUAAGGGAAAUACUAACUUUCUUUCGCAUUAGUAUUAAUUUUGAAGUAGCUACAAAGUAUUUUUAAGAAAUUAUAAUUUUAUGACUGUCUGGCAGGCUCUGUCAGUUUAGCCGCGCCGGACCGUGUCAAGCAUCUAGGAGAGGAGUCCAUGGUGUCCAGGCAUCGGGGCGUCACACCUGUUGAGGAGUGGGGUGGCUUUGAAUGCUGGAAAUGGCUUCAUAGUGAAGUGCCUCCCACAGGGCGGGUGGGUCAGCGUUGACUCUUUCCAGCUGCACACUCAUAUGCCGUGUGUCUUAUUCAGAAGUCACAUUCUUUUCAGUUGGAGAGAAUUGGGCUAAGAUAGAAAAUAACAUGAUUUGUUCCUUAUUAAAGCUUCCCAGCGUAUGAAAUUCUAAGCUGGGUGGGGUGGCUCACACCCGACGUAAUCCCAGCACGUUGGGAGGCCGAGGCAGGUGGAUCACUUGAGGCCAGGAGUUCGAGACCAGCCUGGUCAAGAUGGUGAAACCCCAUCUCUACUAAAAUUACAAAAAUUAGCCGGGUGUCGUGGCACACACCUGUAAUCCCAGCUAUUUGGGAGGCCAAGGCAGGAGAAUUGCCUGAACCCGGGAGGCGGAGGUUGCAGUGAGCUGAGAUCGCACCACUGCACUCCAGCACUCCAGCCUGGGUGACAGAGCAAGACUCUCUCUCAAAAAAAAAAAAAAAAAAAAAUUCUAGACCGAAGUGUACGGCAGUGCCAUCUGGUGGCAAGUGGUACAAAGACAACGCUGAGGGGUAGUGACUCCUGUAGCAGCAGAGACGCCUUGGAGUUUAACCCCCACCAACCAGAGCGUGGGCUGGUAAAGAUGAAAUCUUGCAAGUUUUUUUUUUUUUUAAAUCAUGGUACCUGUUUUAAAAUGAGAAGUUAUUAUUCAUACUGUGUUGCUCAUUUGACAAAAUAAGGUAAGGAUUUCAUAAUCAGGUUGUCUGGGUUUCAGAGCUGUUUUUAAUUGACUGAGUUACCUACAGGCACCCAAUCUAGACCCUAAUUCUGUGGUUGGUGUUCCUCUGUAGAUUUCAAGACAAGUAGUGAUGUCAUUUUCUCCCUGAGCUGUAGGGUGGACCUGGACCCCUCAGAGAUGCUCGACUGCAGGGUCCUGGGGUCCCUAGAGUGGUCCUGCAGCAGCCCCUGGCAAUGAGCUGCCUGAUGAUGAGUCCCAAGGUACAUUGUUCUACUGUUUUAUACCCAGGUAGAAGUUACACAGCAAUUUAGCAAUGUUGUUAACAGACAUACAGAAUUGUGUGUGUGUGUGUGUGUGUGUGUGUGAGUGUUUUGAUAUAAACGUGCAAUUAAAAUUCAAAGUUUAUUUUUUAUCACAAGCACCUUUGAAAUGUACGUGGAAAACGUCGGCUGCUCGUGAGAAUCAUGUGUGACUUACGUUCCUUAUGUUUUAUGGAACUCUCGGAACAGUGUUUUGUUUUUGUUUAGUUUUUGUUUUCGUUUUUUUGAGACGGAGCCUGGCUUUGGCUCCCAGGCUGGAGUCCAGUGGUGUGAUCUCGGCUCACUGCAACCUCCACCUCCCGGGUUCCAGGGAUUCUCCUGCCUCACCCUUUCAAGUAGCUGGGAUUACAGGUACCUCUACCAUGCCUGGCUGAUUUUUUGUAUUUUUAGUAGAGACAGGGUUUCACCAUGUUGGCCAGGCUGGUCUCUGACUCCUGACUAAAAGUGAUCUGCCCACCUCGGCCUCCCAAAGUUCUGGGAUUACGGGCGUGAGCCACUUCACCCGGCCCGGAGCGGUGUAUUUUGAUUGCUGGUGCUUUAACUAUAUUGACCAAGGUGUAUAGUAACCUAUUUAUCACAUUUUACGAAGCAAUUUUAAUCUUAAACACAUCCAGCAAAUGGUGUCCCUGCUGAAACUUUUAACUGGAAACCUCACACCUGGCAGGCAGCACUCUCUGCAGCCGUGCCCUUGUGGAGUCAGCAGGAGCUGGUGUUUUUCAGCCAGACAGAGGCAUAAUAAAGUGACUGAUGUUUACAGAACCCAAAUGAUGUCUUCCUCUCUCUCAAAAUAAACUAACCUAUUCAUAUUGCUGUGAAUGCUUUAUCUUGGAGAUAGAAAAUAUAAUGAUAAAUUCAUCAUGUGUUCAGAAUUCGAUUUGGAGUUGGAAGUGGACAGCCUAAUUUUUAUCUCACCUCCACUAGGACUUUGACCUUCCCAGGGGUCCACACUUUACCUCCUGUAUCUUCAUACGCGUGUGUGGAUGCAUAGAGAUGGAGGUGCUGUAGAGAAGCACAGGCUCACCCGCUCCGUCCAGUGUCACCCACACAUUGGUCCGGGGACCCCUCAGUGCAGAGCCUGAAGUUGGGGGUUUAGGGGUGGAAAAGGCUUCGUGAAAUGUUAAUGAUGCGUACACCUUCCAGAUGGCACAGCACUUUCCCAUGGUCCUCACUGGCCUCAGUCUCCCUGACCGGCAGUGUGAGGGGAUGUAGCUAUAGUGGAGCAUGGUACAAGCGACAUUCAUGAGCUCUGACUUCUUGGUGCCAGGUUGGUGUGAGCCUGGGCCCGGCCCACUCAGCGGCCCACAUUGGCCAGCAUUCAGCUGCACGUGUGUGCUGCGUGCUUCACAUCCUCUAUUGAGAGUUACAGCAAGUGUUAAACGAGGUGAGUUCACAUAACAGGAAUUCUGGAACUGCUUGAAAACUAGGACGAUUGGGCAAUAUCGGCCUUAACUCCACCUGAUGGCAGGUGACCCGGAUAGAAAAUGGCCCUGCGUUUAGCCAGGAUGUGGCUCUCCAGCUUGGCUUCAGUGUGAUCACUUGUCAGUGCGCUUUCUCUUUCGAUAGUGAAAUCCUUCUCUAUACCUAUGUUUUGUUUUGUUUCUUAAGUUGGGAAACAGAAUGGGCCAGGGAGGUUGAGUGACUGAAGACCAAGGGUUGGUGCAGCCUCCUCGCCGCGCUGCGGGGGCUGGGCCGCACAGGCUUCUGCCCUUCUCGGUGUCCAGGCUCCUUGGGUGAUGCUGGAGUUGUCAUGGCCGCAGUUCAGUGUGAGAUUUUUUACCAGGUAUUGCGCUUAAGGGACAUGAUUUUCCAUUUUCUUCGCCCGGACAACUUGAAUGAAAUGGGCACUGUUGAUUCCACUUCUGUCGAGGAGCUUCGGGGCUCAGAGAGGUGAUGACGUGCCCAAGGUGACGCAACUCGUGAACAGCCGUGCCUGCCUUGGGCGCAGCCUCCGGCGCCAGAGCUGGGCUCUUCAACACGGCAUUUAGCGCAGAAAGUCGUGGUUCAGGCAGUAUGGGCCGCUGUGACAAAACACCUAAGACUGGGUAGUUUAUAAAGAACAGACAUUCAGGCCAGGCACGGUGACUCACGCCUGUAAUCCCAGCACUUUGGGAGGCCGAGGCGGGUGGAUCAUUUGAGGUCAGGAGUUUGAAACCAGCCUGGCCAACAUGGUGAAACCCCAUCUCUACUAAAAAAACAAAACUAGCUGGGGGUGGUGGUGCAUGCCUGUGGUCCCAGCUACUUGGGAGGCUAAGGUAGAAGAAUUGCUUGAACCUGGGAGGCAGAGAUUGCAGUGAGCCGAGAUCACGCCAUUGCACUCCAGCCUGGGUGACACAGUGAGACUCCAUCUCAAAAAAAAAAAAAGAACGGACAUCAUUUCUCACAGUUCUGGAGGCUGGAAGUCCAAGAUAAAGGUGUGGGCUGAUUAGUUUCUGCUGGGAACACUGCAUCCUCACGUGGUGGAGGGGAUGGAAGGUCAACAGGCCUCAGCUAGUUCUCCGCUGCCUUUUUAUGAGGCAUUAAGCCAUUUGCAAGAGUAGGGGGCCCCACCUCUUAAUACCACCGCAAUGACAAUUACAAUGUCAUGUGAAUUCUGGAGGGGACACGGUCACACUGCAGCAUCAGCACCCGGUGAAUGUGGUUCUCUUCCCAUGUCCGAAUUUUGUGAGCUCCACACGGGCAGGGUUGCAUCUGUUUUAUUCUCUGAUUGAUUCUAAGCCCCAUGUCCCUGGCACAGGAUGGCUGCUUGGCAGUAGGGAGUGGAUGAACCAGUAGUACCCAGGGCUGCCAGGCAGGGCCCUGCAGGGGACAGACCCAAGGGCUGAUAUGGGGACACCUGCUGAGGGGGGAAUUUACCACGGUAAGGGCAGGGCUGGGAGGCUGGGCAGCCAGUUUCACCCUCGCACAGGCUGCCUGGCAAGACCAGCGGCUGGAGGUGAUGUCCUCAGUAGAGAACGGUGGCCACUGGAAACGUGUGGCCAGAAGGGGAAACGCUCGGGCCUCUGGUGGGGGCCAGCCUGGGGUGGGGUCGGCCAGGGUCAGCUGCCUUUCCUUCAUGCUGGGGAGGAGAUGUUGUGUGCAUGUGAGAAAGCAUUUGAUAGCAUGCCAAAAGUUUCCUCCAUUAUGUGCGUGUCAAGUGUUUGACCAGGUCAGAACUCUUGUUCUAUGCGAAUGUGCUCACGCAGACAGAAGCGGAGGGGCUCCGUCGCUCUGCCCUCACGCCGCUGAACCGCGAGGGUCUCCCGCUCCUCAGGCUUGCGGCUCGGCCGCGAAGUGUGUCAGGUGUGCAUCCUGGGUGCUCCUUUGUGCUCUGUCCUACGGUGACACAGGCGGCGUGGGGUUAGACAGGUACCGGUCAGACUACGGUGACACAGGCGGCGUGCGGUUAGACAGGUACCGGUCAGAUUACGGUGGCACAGGCGGCGUGGGGUUAGACAGGUACCGGUCAGAUUACGGUGGCACAGGCGGCGUGGGGUUAGACAGGUACCGGUCAGAUUACGGUGGCACAGGCGGCGUGGGGUUAGACAGGUACCGGUCAGAUUACGGUGGCACAGGCGGCGUGGGGUUAGACAGGUACCGGUCAGAUUACGGUGGCACAGGCAGCGUGGGGUUAGACAGGUACCGGUCAGAUUACGGUGGCACAGGCGGCGUGGGGUUAGACAGGUACCGGUCAGAUUACGGUGGCACAGGCGGCGUGGGGUUAGACAGGUACCGGUCAGAUUACGGUGACACAGGCGGCGUGGGGUUAGACAGGUACCGGUCAGAUUACGGUGGCACAGGCUGCGUGGGGUUAGACAGGUACCGGUCAGAUUACGGUGGCACAGGCGGCGUGGGGUUAGACAGGUACUGGUCAGAUGCACGGGCUCCCUAAACCCCUGCUGUGGCUUCGGCAGUAAAGACAGGACGCACCCAUGUCACAAGAGGAGCACAGGCAGGGGUGUUGGUGUUGGGGCAGCCCUCAGGGUCUCCAGACCCCAGCCCCACUCACACAGCAGCCUAGGAAGGAAGGGCAGAGUCCCAGGUGUCAGCUGGUGGGUCUCCCAGGAGCUGCCCCUCCCUGGAAGUCACAGGACAGGAAUGACAGAUCAGGGAACUGCAGGAAGCUGCCACCUCUGGGGUCAGAAUAUGCCCAGCCUGCGGGGGCUCUCUAUCGGGGUCUUCGAGAGCCAGACAGCCUGCCUUGUGCUGCAUACCUGGCUUUGCUCUGUGCAGAACCCAGCACACGUGAUUUUGUGUGACAUGCCAGCAGCCUGGCUCCCAGGACAGGAGGCCUGCCCUGGGGGAGGGGCUGCAGGAGGAGGGGGGGCAGGCACCCAUGAGUCUGUCCAGCCUUGUCACAGAUGCAUCGCCCACCCUGCGGUCCUGAUUUCAGCUCACCUCAGAGUAAAUCAGAAUAAACUGCACCCAGACUUUCACGAAUGCAUGUUGACGCUUUCAGUUCACCCCUUUCUUUGCUAACUUUCUUCCUAUUUUCUUCUAAUGCGAGAGCUUAUUAAUUCCAUAUUUAUCAUUUUGAAUAACUUUUCUCCUUUUUAGUAACAAAAUGUACUUCACUCUUAGUAAAAUGUAUUUACUAUUUUAGUAACAAAAAUAUACUUGCCUAAUCAUGUUUAAAAUAUAGUGAUGUGAAAAAUUCA